UUUUUUUUUUUUUUUUUUUUUGAGACGGAAUCUCGCUCUGUCACCCAGGCUGGGGUGCAGUGGGGCGAUCUCAGCUCACUGCAACCUCUGCCUCCCAGGUUCAAGUAAUUCUUCUGCCUCAGCCUCCAGAGUAGCUGGGACUACAGGCGCCCGCCACCACGCCUAGCUAAUUUUUUUUGUUUUUGUCUUUUUAGUACAGACGGGGUUUCACCAUGUUAGCCAGAGUGGUCUCGAUCUCCUGACCUUGUGAUCUGCCUGCCUUGGCCUCCCAAAGUGCUGGUCUUGAACUGCUGGGCUCAAAUGAUCCACCUGCCUUAGCCUUCUAAAGUUCUGGGAUUACAGGCGUGAGCCACCACACCCAGCCCUAUUUUGUACUAUGUUUAUGUUUCUGUUUAGGUUUUCUGUCUUUUCUGGUUUCAGUUCGCAUCGGUUAUACUUGCUAAGUUUUCUAUUUGCAUGGGGUUUAACAAAAUAGUCUGUACUAUCCAUAUUUUCUAUCUAUAGUUAUUUCCAAAUAUCUUUUUCUUUUUUACUCUUACUUCUUUUAAGUUUUUCCUUAAGAAUCCACUCAUGAAUUUAUUAUUUCUCUUUUUCUGUUUGUAAUACAUUAAUUUCUUUUUCCUAUUUUUACUAAUUUUCUGUUUUUCUUUCCUUUUUCUUUCUUUCUUUUUUUUUUUUUUUUGAGACAGAGUCUCACUCUGUUGCCCAGGCUGGAGUGCAGUGGCACAAUAUUGGUUCACUGCAACUUCCUCCUCCUGGGUUCAAGCAUUUCUCCUGCCUCAGCCUCCCGAGUAGCUGGGAUUACAGGCGCACACCACCACACCCGGCUAAUUUUGUAUUUUUAGUAGAGAUGGGGUUUCUCCAUGUUGGCCAGGCUGGUCUCGAACUCCUAACCUCAAGUGAUCUGCCCACCUCGGCCUCCCAAAGUGCUGGGAUUACAGGCGUGAGUCACCACACCCGGUCUGUUUUUCUUAUAUUUACUUUUUCUUAUGUUAAUUACUUUGAGUGCUUAUUUUAUUACUUUUUUUAAAAUGAUGUAAGCUUUUAUGCUAAAACUUCAUUCUCCAAGCAUUAAUUUUCCCUGGCCAAAGGGUUUGUUCAAACCAAUAGAUUUUGAAAUUUACAAGUGAAAGGUUUUGUUUUUGUUCUGUCAUUUCUAUGUGUUGGGUUUUUUGUUUUUUUGGUCAGAGUAUUUUGUCCAUCCUUUACUACUUUGUGGAACAGGCUACUGUAUGGGCUGAUUUUCAGAAUGUUCUUUGGGCAUUUAAAAAGGUGGUUUAUAAUCUAUUUUCAAGAUAUAGGAUAAACUGAUUAAUAAAAUAUGUUAUAAAUGUGUAUACAUUUUUCUUUUUAUUUAUAUUGUAUUUUAUGGAUUUGAAUUCAGAGGUUGAGAGUGGUUGUUUUCUCAGUUACUAACGGGGUUCUGAAAUGUUACCCCCAGUAUGUUAUACCCAUACUUCCCCUUCUGACUUCUGAUACUAGUAAGAUCACUGCUUUUUUAUUAAAGCAUUUGUAAGCAUUUACGUAACUAUAACACUGUAAGCAUUGUUGACUGGUAAACCAAAUGAUUUUCUAUGACUCUGUUUGAUUUCUUGUAUAACCUUUUGCUUUUCUUUUAAUUAAUAUUUGCUUCUUUGUUUUGUUUGCUUAGUUUUCCAUUUUUGUGUUUUGAUUCUUCCCAAGCUUUCAGACAGAACUGUAAAACCUAGAAGUCUAAGUUGGAAGUAACUUAUGGUUAGGAUUAUCCAUUGUCUUGCAAUCUGAUGCCUUUUUGAUGUGAAGAAGCCUGGGAAGUUUAUAAACAGAUAAAGACGCAACAUGAAAGACUUGUAAGUUAAGUCUCAUCUUUCUCUGUGAAAAGACAGACUGAGGGAAAAUUUAGGAAACAAAGUAUUUCCUCUGAACAGUCAUUGAUUCUUCAAGACUACCCUUCUGUGUAUGGAACUCAGUUUAAAAGAAUUUGAAACCUAAUUUAUAUACAAUCUAUACCUAAAUAUGGGAGAAGCUAUAUAAGAACCAUUAAGAAUAUAAAGAGAAUGUUACAUUUUAUCCCUUUUUGUAAUCAUCUCAUCUCAGGGUAAUCAAUGUGAGAAAAGUCUUCCAUCAUAAAUUUAACUUCAUUAGAUACCUGAGAAUUAAUAUUGAAAAUACACCAUAUGAAUUUAGUGAAUGUGGGAAAGCUUUCAUCCUUAUUACAUCUUAUUUGAUACUAGGGAAAUCUCCUGAUUAAAUUCACAUGCAUGAUAGGCAUGUUGGAAAGUCUUCAGCAUGAAUCAGAUCUCCUUCAGCAUGAUCAAAUUCAUACUGGAGAGAAACCUUAUGAAUGUAAUGAAUGUAGAAAAACUUUUAGCCUGAAGCAAAACCUUGUAGAGCAUAAGAAAAUGCAUACUGGAGAGAAAUCUCAUGAAUGCACUGAAUGUGGUAAAGUGUGCUCUCGAGUCUCAUCUCUUACUCUACACCUUAGAAGUCACACAGGAAAGAAGGCAUAUAAAUGUAAUAAAUGUGGAAAAGCCUUCAGCCAGAAGGAAAACUUCCUUUCUCAUCAGAAACAUCACACUGGAGAGAAACCUUAUGAAUGUGAAAAAGUUUCUAUUCAGAUGCCAACCAUCAUCAGACACCAGAAAAAUCAUACAGGAACCAAACCCUAUGCAUGUAAGGAAUGUGGCAAAGCCUUUAACGGCAAAGCAUAUCUCACUGAGCAUGAGAAAAUUCAUACUGGAGAAAAACCAUUUGAAUGUAAUCAGUGUGGAAGAGCCUUCAGCCAGAAGCAAUACCUCAUUAAACAUCAGAACAUCCAUACUGGAAAGAAGCCCUUUAAAUGUAGUGAGUGUGGAAAAGCUUUUAGCCAGAAGGAAAACCUCAUUAUACAUCAGAGAAUCCAUACUGGAGAGAAACCUUAUGAAUGUAAAGGGUGUGGGAAAGCUUUCAUUCAGAAGUCAAGCCUCAUUAGACACCAGAGAAGUCACACAGGAGAGAAACCUUAUACGUGUAAGGAAUGUGGGAAAGCCUUCAGUGGCAAGUCAAAUCUCACAGAGCAUGAGAAAAUUCAUAUUGGAGAGAAACCCUACAAAUGUAAUGAAUGUGGAACAAUCUUCAGGCAGAAGCAAUACCUCAUUAAACAUCACAAUAUUCAUACAGGAGAGAAACCCUAUGAAUGUAAUAAAUGUGGAAAAGCCUUCUCUCGAAUCACAUCACUUAUUGUACAUGUGAGAAUUCAUACAGGUGAUAAGCCUUAUGAGUGUAAGGUCUGUGGGAAAGCCUUCUGUCAAAGCUCAUCUCUUACUGUGCAUAUGAGAAGCCAUACAGGUGAGAAACCCUAUGGUUGUAAUGAAUGUGGGAAAGCCUUUUCUCAGUUCUCAACCCUUGCUCUGCACAUGAGAAUCCAUACUGGUGAAAAACCUUAUCAGUGUAGUGAAUGUGGGAAAGCUUUCAGCCAAAAGUCACAUCACAUUAGACACCAGAGAAUUCAUACUCAUUAAAGUUCUCUAUGAAUGCCUUGGAUUUAGCAAAACGUUCAGCAGAUUUUACACUUAAUAGUGUAUUGGAAAAUUCAUUUUACAUUAAAGUGACAUGAAUGUGGGAAGUCCUUCAGCAGCAAUUCAAAACUUAAAUACUAUGAUGUUUAAUAAGUAUUAUAGUGUAAAGAAAACCCGUACCCCCAAAACUCCCACAACAAGCAUUAUCAAUGCUGUACUUCUAGGAGUAUACUCAUUAAAGUUAGGAUCUAGUCAUGGACACUACUUAAUGUGUUCCUGGAAGGCCUACAGAUGCAUUAAGAAAUAGAUAUGAGAUGUAUGAGGAUUUGAAAUUAAGAGACAAAAUUAUCAUUUUUGUGAUGUUUUGCUACAUAUAUGAAUUGUAAAACUAGAAUCAUCAAAAUUAUUUGUUGUUGAAGCAGUCAUAAAACUGAGACUGAGACAGAAUAUUGAAUUCAGAAAUGUGUGCAUGAAUAUAUGGGGAAUUGGUAAUUGAUAGAGGCGGUAUCCCAGAUUGGUGGGGAAAUCAUGGAUUACUUAAAAAUUAAUUGACUCUUCAUAUGGAAAAAUAAUAUCUCCCAUCAUAAUAUAAAAUAUUUUUCUUAUGAAUUCUUAAAGUACUAAAGACUAAAAUGCAAAAAGCAAUACUUAAUAAUAUAACAGUUUUAUAAGAAGAUGUUUUUAAAACCUUAGGGCAGGAAAGAACUUCUAAAACAUUCCAGAAUACCCGGUAGUUCCACUCUUGAGUAUGGUAGUCCCCUAUUUUCUGCAAGAGAUGGACUCUAAGACCCCCAGUGGAUACCUAAAACCCAGAUAGGACCAAACUCUAUGUCUAUGUUUUUUUCUUAUAUAUACAUACCUAUGAUAAAAUUUAGUUUACAGAUUAGACACAGCAAGAGAUUUAAAACAAUAAUAAACAUAAUAUGGAACAAUUAUAACAAUAUACUGUAAUCAUAAAAGUUAUGUGAAUAUGAUCUUUCUCUCAGAAUACCUUAUUGUACUGUUCUCAACUAUUUAUGAACUGUGGUGACUACAGGUAACUGAAACCAUGGAAAGCAAAGCUGUGGAUAAGGGGGAACUACUAUAUAUAUGCAUCUACCCAAGAAACAUGAACACAGGGAGUCAUGUACUGGUCUAUAGCUGUAUAGUUCAUUGCACCAUGAGUUAUAGUAGCCAGAAGUUGGGAAACAAAUGCUGUCUCUUGUGAAAUAGAUGAAUAAAAUGUGAUAGUAACAUAGUAGAGUACUCUCUAGCAGUUAAGUGACAAAUUAAGUCUAUAUAUUAACAGAAAUAUUUUUAAAAAAUUAGAGUGAAGAAAAAUGAUGAACAUAUUGUAAUGAUGCUUCUGUGAAUUUGAAUAAAAUCAACACUAACCAGCCCUAGUACUAAGAAUUGGUUAUGGAUAAAUUAUGUAAAACUAAAGAAUGGAUUGAAAGGAUAUGUAUAUACUCAGUUCCCAAAAGUGGAGUGGUUACCUCUAGGAAGAAAGGAGGUGGAAGGGAAAUGUUACCAAGCAUGGUAGUUAAAGGAUACUUCAAUUUUGUAUCUAUUUCUUAUUAAAAAGAAACAUUCUAAGUAAACAUAACGAAAUAUUAAUUCUGGGUGGUGGUAAUAUUUGUGUUCAUUCUAUCAUUCGUGCUAUUUAUUUCCUUAAACUUCUGAAAGUUAAAAAGUCCAGAUAGGAGUGAGGAAGCUGUACAUGAAACAUAAUGGACUUACAUUCCUAGUCAGAUACUAAUAUUCUGUAGAAGAUAUUUCUAAAAUCUUAUCUUUAAAAUAUGAAAUAAUUUUUAAUUGGGGUGGCAACUUAAAUUCAAUUAAAAUAACUCAUGUGUCACAAGAGUAAAUUUUACAUAAUCUGUACGUAGUUCUAAUCUGUAUAUAGUCUUGGAGGUUAUGAUUUGCCACAGAUUGGUUGGAUCACAUACAUUUAAGGAUCAUAUUAUUAAAUAAUAUAUGCACAGACAUGGAGAGAAUUAGUUUUUACUAAAACAUUUAUCAGAAAUUUUAAUACUCUGCAUAACCAGUAUUAGCAUUAGAAAUUAGCCACUUUUAAAAUGAGAAAACUGUGUCACUCUUCAAUUUUUUUAUAAGCCAUUGAGGAAAACAUUAACUCCUGGAUUUCAGCUUCACUUUUAACCUGCAGACUAAAUUUCUUUCUCAAUUAUGUCAGACACACCCAAGUCAAUCCCAACCCCCUUGUUACCUUGGGAAGACCGUGCUGAAAAAGGAGAUCUUCCACCUAAACAGUGUUCUCUUAUUUGAAGCAAAUCUUUUUGAGAAUUUGUUUACUUGAUUUCUUUCCACAAUAAACUGACAGAGAACGCUACUAAUGAUUUUUUUUUUUUUUUGAGACGGAGUUUUGUUCUUGUUGCCCAGGCUGCAGUGCAAUGGCACAAUCUUGGCUCACUGCAACCUCUGCCUCACAGGUUCAAGUGGUUCUCCUGCCUCAGCCUCUUGAGUAGCUGGGAUUACAGGCAUGCGCCACCAUGCCCGGCUAAUUUUGUAUUUUUAGUAGAGACGGAGUUGCACCAUGUUGGCCAGGCUGGUCUUGAAUUCCUGACCUCAGGUGAUCCACCUGCUUCGGCCUCCCAAAGUGCUAGGAUUACAGGUGUGAGCCACCACGCCUGGCUAAUUUUGUAUUUUUAGUAGAGAUGGGGUUUCUCCAAAGGCUGGUCUUGAACUCCCGACCUCAGGUGAUCCGCCCACCUUGGCCUCCCGAAGUGCUGGGAUUACAGGCGUGAGCCACCGUGCCCGGCCUGAUGUUUUUGAAUGAUUAUGAAAAUGGGUAUACAGCAUUAAAACCUUAGACUGAUUUUAAAUAUAUUAAUUUCUUUUAAACUCAAUAUAAUGUUAAUAUUACUGUAGCACUUACUAGCAUUUCUGAAGGUUGGUCUUGAGAUAAGAUUGAAAAUGACAGUUGUUGAUUUUCUGAGGUAAUAUACCCAAAUAAAAUAUAUGUAUGUGUACAUGAAUCUAAACUGUCUUCUUCUGUUCCUCAUUUUGCUUUACUUAAAUAAUCUUUCAUAUUUUUUAAGUGUUUUGCCCAUGUGCUUGGGUAGCCUUGAAGUCACCAGAAUAACUAGGACUCAAAUUCAGACCAAACCAGGACUAGCUUUUUGUGCCAUGAGUUAGCCAUGGUCCUGGACCCAGCAAAAAGAAUGAUUAUGAUGGUCAGAGUAAGAUGAGCAAUUGCAACAUAAUAUUCUCUAAUAUUGUAUACUGUAAAUUUAUUCAGCUGCCCUCGUUUACUCACAGUUUGCUUAUUUGCCACCAUAAGAAAUGGUACAAUAAAAAUUCAUGUAAUCACCCCUUA